AGUCCAGCAGCCACCAUCACCACCACUGCGGUUGCUGCUGCAGCUGCAGCUGCUGCUCUCCCUCCGGCUGCUUCUUCGCGUGGCCAGCAGCGAAUGGAGCGAUGGAGCCCAGACUGUUCUGCUGGACCACUCUCUUUCUCCUGGCCGGGUGGUGCCUGCCAGGGUUGCCCUGCCCCAGCCGGUGCCUUUGCUUUAAGAGCACCGUCCGCUGCAUGCACUUGAUGCUGGACCACAUUCCUCAGGUACCACAGCAGACCACAGUUCUGUACAAACAACCAGCAUUGUAUUUUUGGUAAUAAAAUCAAAACAGUGGAUUCUGGAGUUAGAGUGAGGACAAGUUUUAGAAGAGUGUAAAGGACCACGAUCAAGUGCAUCCUAGAAACAGCUUGUUCCAUCUAAAAUGUUUAAUUCCACUAAAGAUCUUGAUGAGACUUGAGGUUUAACAGAAUAAGAGAAAUUCCAGGGAGCGCCUUCAAGAAACUCAAGAAUUUGAACACACUUCUGCUGAACAACAACCACAUCAGAAAGAUUUCCAGAAAUGCUUUUGAAGGACUUGAAAAUUUGCUAUAUCUGUACCUGUAUAAGAAUGAAAUCCAUGCACUAGAUAAGCAAACAUUUAAAGGACUCAUAUCUUUGGAACAUCUGUAUAUUCAUUUCAACCAACUAGAAAUGCUACAGCCAGAGACCUUUGGAGACCUUCUGAGAUUAGAGCGACUAUUUUUGCAUAACAACAAAUUAUCUAAAAUUCCAGCUGGGAGCUUUUCUAAUCUGGAUUCAUUAAAAAGAUUGCGUCUGGAUUCCAACGCCCUGGUUUGUGACUGUGAUCUGAUGUGGCUGGGGGAGCUUUUACAAGGCUUUGCCCAACACGGCCACACCCAGGCUGCGGCUACCUGCGAAUAUCCCAGGAGACUCCAUGGGCGUGCAGUUGCUUCAGUAACAGUAGAGGAAUUCAAUUGCCAGAGCCCCCGAAUUACUUUUGAGCCGCAGGAUGUGGAGGUACCAUCAGGAAAUACCGUCUACUUCACCUGCCGGGCGGAAGGAAACCCCAAACCUGAGAUUAUUUGGAUACACAACAACCACUCAUUGGAUUUGGAAGAUGAUACUCGACUUAAUGUGUUUGAUGAUGGCACACUCAUGAUCCGAAACACCAGAGAGUCAGACCAAGGUGUCUAUCAGUGCAUGGCCAGAAAUUCCGCUGGGGAAGCCAAGACACAGAGUGCCAUGCUCAGAUACUCCAGUCUUCCAGCCAAACCAAGCUUUGUAAUCCAGCCUCAGGACACAGAGGUUUUAAUUGGCACCAGCACAACUUUGGAAUGUAUGGCCACAGGCCACCCACACCCUCUUAUCACUUGGACCAGGGACAAUGGAUUGGAGCUGGAUGGAUCCAGGCACGUGGCAACGUCCAGUGGACUUUACUUACAGAACAUCACACAACGGGAUCAUGGUCGAUUUACCUGUCAUGCCAACAAUAGCCACGGCACUGUUCAAGCUGCAGCAAACAUAAUUGUACAAGCUCCUCCACAAUUUACAGUAACCCCCAAGGAUCAAGUGGUGCUGGAAGAACAUGCUGUAGAGUGGCUCUGUGAAGCUGACGGCAACCCACCUCCUGUUAUUGUCUGGACAAAAACAGGAGGGCAGCUCCCUGUGGAAGGCCAGCAUACAGUUCUCUCCUCUGGCACUUUGAGAAUUGACCGUGCAGCACAGCACGAUCAAGGCCAAUAUGAAUGUCAAGCAGUCAGUUCGUUGGGGGUGAAAAAGGUGUCUGUGCAGCUGACUGUAAAACCCAAAGCUCUUGCAGUGUUUACUCAACUUCCUCAGGAUACAAGUGUCGAGGUUGGAAAGAAUAUAAACAUUUCAUGUCAUGCUCAAGGAGAACCACAGCCCAUAAUUACUUGGAAUAAGGAAGGUGUGCAGAUUACUGAGAGUGGUAAAUUCCAUGUGGAUGAUGAAGGCACGCUGACUAUCUACGACGCAGGGUUCCCUGACCAGGGAAGAUAUGAAUGUGUGGCUCGGAAUUCUUUUGGCCUUGCUGUGACCAACAUGUUUCUUACAGUCACGGCUAUACAGGGUAGACAAGCUGGCGAUGACUUUGUUGAAUCUUCCAUUCUUGAUGCUGUACAGAGAGUUGACAGUGCAAUUAACUCCACACGAAGACAUUUGUUUUCACAAAAACCUCACACCUCCAGUGACCUGCUGGCUCAAUUUCAUUACCCGCGUGACCCACUGAUUGUGGAAAUGGCAAGAGCAGGGGAGAUUUUUGAGCACACGCUGCAGCUGAUACGGGAACGUGUGAAGCAGGGGCUCACUGUGGACUUGGAAGGCAAAGAAUUCCGGUACAAUGACUUGGUGUCCCCGCGCUCCCUCAGCCUCAUCGCCAAUUUAUCUGGAUGCACAGCUCGCAGGCCUCUGCCAAACUGCUCCAACCGGUGUUUCCAUGCGAAGUACCGCGCCCACGACGGCACGUGCAACAACCUGCAGCAGCCCACGUGGGGCGCGGCGCUGACCGCCUUCGCGCGCCUGCUGCAGCCAGCCUACCGGGACGGCAUCCGCGCGCCCCGCGGGCUCGGCCUUCCUGUGGGCUCCCGCCAGCCCCUCCCGCCGCCCCGGCUGGUCGCCACAGUGUGGGCGCGCGCGGCGGCCGUCACCCCCGACCACAGCUACACGCGCAUGCUCAUGCACUGGGGCUGGUUUCUAGAGCACGACUUGGACCACACAGUGCCUGCGCUGAGCACAGCCCGCUUCUCGGAUGGGCGGCCGUGCAGCUCCGUCUGCACCAACGACCCUCCUUGUUUCCCCAUGAACACCCGGCACGCCGACCCCCGGGGCACCCACGCGCCCUGCAUGCUCUUCGCGCGCUCCAGCCCCGCGUGUGCCAGCGGCCGUCCCUCUGCGACGGUGGAUUCAGUCUAUGCACGAGAGCAGAUCAACCAGCAAACAGCCUACAUCGAUGGCUCCAACGUUUACGGGAGCUCGGAGCGGGAAUCCCAGGCUCUCAGAGACCCUUCGGUGCCUCGGGGUCUCCUGAAGACAGGCUUUCCUUGGCCUCCCUCCGGAAAGCCCUUAUUGCCCUUUUCUACAGGCCCACCCACCGAGUGCGCGCGACAGGAGCAGGAGAGCCCCUGUUUCCUGGCCGGGGACCACCGGGCCAACGAGCAUCUGGCUCUGGCCGCCAUGCACACCCUGUGGUUCCGGGAACACAACAGGAUGGCCACGGAGCUGUCCGCCCUGAACCCCCACUGGGAGGGAAACACGGUUUACCAGGAAGCCAGGAAGAUCGUGGGCGCGGAGCUGCAGCACAUCACCUACAGCCACUGGCUGCCUAAGGUCCUGGGGGACCCUGGCACUAGGAUGCUGAGGGGUUACCGAGGCUACAACCCCAACGUGAAUGCAGGCAUCAUUAACUCUUUUGCUACUGCAGCCUUUAGAUUUGGCCACACAUUAAUCAAUCCUAUUCUUUACCGACUGAAUGCCACCUUAGGUGAAAUUUCCGAAGGCCACCUUCCGUUCCAUAAAGCGCUCUUUUCACCGUCCAGAAUAAUCAAGGAAGGUGGGAUAGACCCGGUUCUCCGGGGGCUGUUUGGCGUGGCUGCUAAAUGGCGGGCACCCUCCUACCUUCUCAGUCCUGAGCUGACCCAGAGGCUCUUCUCCGCGGCUUAUUCUGCGGCCGUGGAUUCGGCUGCCACCAUCAUUCAAAGGGGUAGAGACCACGGGAUCCCACCAUAUGUUGACUUCAGAGUUUUCUGUAAUUUGACUUCAGUUAAGAACUUUGAGGAUCUUCAAAAUGAAAUUAAAGAUUCAGAGAUUAGACAAAAACUGAGAAAGUUGUACGGCUCUCCAGGUGACAUUGACCUCUGGCCCGCCCUUAUGGUUGAAGACCUGAUUCCUGGUACAAGAGUGGGACCAACACUUAUGUGCCUGUUUGUUACCCAGUUUCAGCGGCUAAGAGAUGGAGAUAGGUUCUGGUAUGAAAACCCUGGAGUAUUUACCCCGGCACAACUCACUCAGCUGAAGCAGGCGUCCCUGAGCCGGGUGCUUUGUGACAAUGGUGACAGCAUUCAGCAAGUGCAGGCUGAUGUCUUUGUAAAGGCAGAAUACCCACAGGAUUACCUGAACUGCAGCGAGAUCCCGAAGGUGGACCUGCGAGUGUGGCAAGACUGCUGUGCAGACUGUAGGAGUAGAGGACAGUUCAGAGCAGUGACGCAAGAGUCUCAAAAGAAACGCUCAGCUCAAUACAGCUAUCCUGUUGAUAAGGAUAUGGAGUUAAGUCAUCUAAGAAGUAGGCAACAAGAUAAAAUAUAUGUGGGUGAAGAUGCUAGAAAUGUGACAGUUCUGGCAAAAACAAAGUUCUCCCAAGAUUUCAGCACGUUUGCAGCGGAAAUUCAGGAAACCAUCACAGCACUCAGAGAGCAGAUAAACAAGCUGGAGGCACGCCUGAGGCAGGCAGGGUGUACAGAUGUUAGAGGGGUUCCAAGGAAGGCCGAGGAGCGCUGGAUGAAAGAAGACUGCACUCACUGCAUUUGUGAGAGUGGCCAGGUCACCUGUGUGGUGGAGAUUUGUCCCCCGGCUCCCUGUCCCAGUCCUGAAUUGGUGAAAGGAACCUGCUGUCCAGUUUGCAGAGACCGAGGAAUGCCAAGUGAUUCCCCAGAGAAGCGCUAAUAAAAGUUUUGUGCUGUUGAGCCCCAAAUGGGAAAUUUCUCAGGAAGAGACAUUUAGGACUUCAGAACUUUUAACUUGUAGUCACAUUGUUGAUAUGGAAACCACUGACUUAAGCAACUUAGUUCAUCUAAUCUUACAUAUACUUACGAUCUUUUAUUUUUUCAUUUUCUAACAUACCUUGAAAUAAUUCAAAACUAAAAGCAAUAAAGUGCAUAUGAAGUGUUUGAUCAUAAGAAAUAUUUCUUACUGUAAGCUGUCAGUUUUAUAUGCCACACCUGGAAAUAAAAAGAAUAUCAUGGAAUAUUUAAAAAAUA